AUUCUCUGAGCCGCUGCUGCCCCUGUGGGAAGGGACCUCGAGUGUGAAGCAUCCUUCCCUGUAGCUGCUGUCCAGUCUGCCCGCCAGACCCUCUGGAGAAGCCCCUGCCCCCCAGCAUGGGUUUCUGCCGCAGCGCCCUGCACCCGCUGUCUCUCCUGGUGCAGGCCAUCAUGCUGGCCAUGACCCUGGCCCUGGGUACCUUGCCUGCCUUCCUACCCUGUGAGCUCCAGCCCCACGGCCUGGUGAACUGCAACUGGCUGUUCCUGAAGUCUGUGCCCCACUUCUCCAUGGCAGCACCCCGUGGCAAUGUCACCAGCCUUUCCUUGUCCUCCAACCGCAUCCACCACCUCCAUGAUUCUGACUUUGCCCACCUGCCCAGCCUGCGGCAUCUCAACCUCAAGUGGAACUGCCCGCCGGUUGGCCUCAGCCCCAUGCACUUCCCCUGCCACAUGACCAUCGAGCCCAGCACCUUCUUGGCUGUGCCCACCCUGGAAGAGCUAAACCUGAGCUACAACAACAUCAUGACUGUGCCUGCGCUGCCCAAAUCCCUCAUAUCCCUGUCCCUCAGCCAUACCAACAUCCUGAUGCUAGACUCUGCCAGCCUCGCCGGCCUGCAUGCCCUGCGCUUCCUAUUCAUGGACGGCAACUGUUAUUACAAGAACCCCUGCAGGCAGGCACUGGAGGUGGCCCCGGGUGCCCUCCUUGGCCUGGGCAACCUCACCCACCUGUCACUCAAGUACAACAACCUCACUGUGGUGCCCCGCAACCUGCCUUCCAGCCUGGAGUAUCUGCUGUUGUCCUACAACCGCAUCGUCAAACUGGCGCCUGAGGACCUGGCCAAUCUGACCGCCCUGCGUGUGCUCGAUGUGGGCGGAAAUUGCCGCCGCUGCGACCACGCUCCCAACCCCUGCAUGGAGUGCCCUCGUCACUUCCCCCAGCUACAUCCCGAUACCUUCAGCCACCUGAGCCGUCUUGAAGGCCUGGUGUUGAAGGACAGUUCUCUCUCCUGGCUGAAUGCCAGUUGGUUCCGUGGGCUGGGAAACCUCCGAGUGCUGGACCUGAGUGAGAACUUCCUCUACAAAUGCAUCACUAAAACCAAGGCCUUCCAGGGCCUAACACAGCUGCGCAAGCUUAACCUGUCCUUCAAUUACCAAAAGAGGGUGUCCUUUGCCCACCUGUCUCUGGCCCCUUCCUUCGGGAGCCUGGUCGCCCUGAAGGAGCUGGACAUGCACGGCAUCUUCUUCCGCUCACUCGAUGAGACCACGCUCCGGCCACUGGCCCGCCUGCCCAUGCUCCAGACUCUGCGUCUGCAGAUGAACUUCAUCAACCAGGCCCAGCUCGGCAUCUUCAGGGCCUUCCCUGGCCUGCGCUACGUGGACCUGUCGGACAACCGCAUCAGCGGAGCUUCGGAGCUGACAGCCACCAUGGGGGAGGCAGAUGGAGGGGAGAAGGUCUGGCUGCAGCCUGGGGACCUUGCUCCGGCCCCAGUGGACACUCCCAGCUCUGAAGACUUCAGGCCCAACUGCAGCACCCUCAACUUCACCUUGGAUCUGUCACGGAACAACCUGGUGACCGUGCAGCCGGAGAUGUUUGCCCAGCUCUCGCACCUGCAGUGCCUGCGCCUGAGCCACAACUGCAUCUCGCAGGCAGUCAAUGGCUCCCAGUUCCUGCCGCUGACCGGUCUGCAGGUGCUAGACCUGUCCCACAAUAAGCUGGACCUCUACCACGAGCACUCAUUCACGGAGCUACCGCGACUGGAGGCCCUGGACCUCAGCUACAACAGCCAGCCCUUUGGCAUGCAGGGCGUGGGCCACAACUUCAGCUUCGUGGCUCACCUGCGCACCCUGCGCCACCUCAGCCUGGCCCACAACAACAUCCACAGCCAAGUGUCCCAGCAGCUCUGCAGUACGUCGCUGCGGGCCCUGGACUUCAGCGGCAAUGCACUGGGCCAUAUGUGGGCCGAGGGAGACCUCUAUCUGCACUUCUUCCAAGGCCUGAGCGGUUUGAUCUGGCUGGACUUGUCCCAGAACCGCCUGCACACCCUCCUGCCCCAAACCCUGCGCAACCUCCCCAAGAGCCUACAGGUGCUGCGUCUCCGUGACAAUUACCUGGCCUUCUUUAAGUGGUGGAGCCUCCACUUCCUGCCCAAACUGGAAGUCCUCGACCUGGCAGGAAACCAGCUGAAGGCCCUGACCAAUGGCAGCCUGCCUGCUGGCACCCGGCUCCGGAGGCUGGAUGUCAGCUGCAACAGCAUCAGCUUCGUGGCCCCCGGCUUCUUUUCCAAGGCCAAGGAGCUGCGAGAGCUCAACCUUAGCGCCAACGCCCUCAAGACAGUGGACCACUCCUGGUUUGGGCCCCUGGCGAGUGCCCUGCAAAUACUAGAUGUAAGCGCCAACCCUCUGCACUGCGCCUGUGGGGCGGCCUUUAUGGACUUCCUGCUGGAGGUGCAGGCUGCCGUGCCCGGUCUGCCCAGCCGGGUGAAGUGUGGCAGUCCGGGCCAGCUCCAGGGCCUCAGCAUCUUUGCACAGGACCUGCGCCUCUGCCUGGAUGAGGCCCUCUCCUGGGACUGUUUCGCCCUCUCGCUGCUGGCUGUGGCUCUGGGCCUGGGUGUGCCCAUGCUGCAUCACCUCUGUGGCUGGGACCUCUGGUACUGCUUCCACCUGUGCCUGGCCUGGCUUCCCUGGCGGGGGCGGCAAAGUGGGCGAGAUGAGGAUGCCCUGCCCUACGAUGCCUUCGUGGUCUUCGACAAAACGCAGAGCGCAGUGGCAGACUGGGUGUACAACGAGCUUCGGGGGCAGCUGGAGGAGUGCCGUGGGCGCUGGGCACUCCGCCUGUGCCUGGAGGAACGCGACUGGCUGCCUGGCAAAACCCUCUUUGAGAACCUGUGGGCCUCGGUCUAUGGCAGCCGCAAGACGCUGUUUGUGCUGGCCCACACGGACCGGGUCAGUGGUCUCUUGCGCGCCAGCUUCCUGCUGGCCCAGCAGCGCCUGCUGGAGGACCGCAAGGACGUCGUGGUGCUGGUGAUCCUGAGCCCUGACGGCCGCCGCUCCCGCUACGUGCGGCUGCGCCAGCGCCUCUGCCGCCAGAGUGUCCUCCUCUGGCCCCACCAGCCCAGUGGUCAGCGCAGCUUCUGGGCCCAGCUGGGCAUGGCCCUGACCAGGGACAACCACCACUUCUAUAACCGGAACUUCUGCCAGGGACCCACGGCCGAAUAGCCGUGAGCCGGAAUCCUGCACGGUGCCACCUCCACACUCACCUCACCUCUGCCUGCCUGGUCUGACCCUCCCCUGCUCGCCUCCCUCACCCCACACCUGACACAGAGCAGGCACUCAAUAAAUGCUACCGAAGGCUA